GGCGGCGGCGGCUGCUCGUGUCGGCUCCGGGCGGCCCCCGCGCCGCAGCCCGCGCCGUGUCCGCGGCGGAGCCGCCCAGGUGCGCAGGAGGAUGGUGGCGCGGCCCUAGGCCCACGCUCCGCACCAUGACCUGCUGGCUGUGCGUCCUGAGCCUGCCCCUGCUCCUGCUGCCCGCGGCGCCGCCCCCGGCUGGAGGCUGCCCGGCCCGCUGCGAGUGCACCGUGCAGACCCGCGCGGUGGCCUGCACGCGCCGCCGCCUGACCGCCGUGCCCGACGGCAUCCCGGCCGAGACCCGCCUGCUGGAGCUCAGCCGCAACCGCAUCCGCUGCCUGAACCCGGGCGACCUGGCCGCGCUGCCCGCGCUGGAGGAGCUGGACCUGAGCGAGAACGCCAUCGCGCACGUGGAGCCCGGCGCCUUCGCCAACCUGCCGCGCCUGCGCGUCCUGCGUCUCCGUGGCAACCAGCUGAAGCUCAUCCCGCCCGGGGUCUUCACGCGCCUGGACAACCUCACGCUGCUGGACCUGAGCGAGAACAAGCUGGUAAUCCUGCUGGACUACACUUUCCAGGACCUGCACAGCCUGCGCCGGCUGGAAGUGGGCGACAACGACCUGGUAUUCGUCUCGCGCCGCGCCUUCGCGGGGCUGCUGGCCCUGGAGGAGCUGACCCUGGAGCGCUGCAACCUCACGGCUCUGUCCGGGGAGUCGCUGGGCCAUCUGCGCAGCCUGGGCGCCCUGCGGCUGCGCCACCUGGCCAUCGCCUCCCUGGAGGACCAGAACUUCCGCAGGCUGCCCGGGCUGCUGCACCUGGAGAUUGACAACUGGCCGCUGCUGGAGGAGGUGGCGGCGGGCAGCCUGCGGGGCCUGAACCUGACCUCGCUGUCGGUCACCCACACCAACAUCACCGCCGUGCCGGCCGCCGCGCUGCGGCACCAGGCGCACCUCACCUGCCUCAAUCUGUCGCACAACCCCAUCAGCACGGUGCCGCGGGGGUCGUUCCGGGACCUGGUCCGCCUGCGCGAGCUGCACCUGGCCGGGGCCCUGCUGGCUGUGGUGGAGCCGCAGGCCUUCCUGGGCCUGCGCCAGAUCCGCCUGCUCAACCUCUCCAACAACCUGCUCUCCACGUUGGAGGAGAGCACCUUCCACUCGGUGAACACGCUAGAGACGCUGCGCGUGGACGGGAACCCGCUGGCCUGCGACUGUCGCCUGCUGUGGAUCGUGCAGCGUCGCAAGACCCUCAACUUCGACGGGCGGCUGCCGGCCUGCGCCACCCCGGCCGAGGUGCGCGGCGACGCGCUGCGAAACCUGCCGGACUCCGUGCUGUUCGAGUACUUCGUGUGCCGCAAACCCAAGAUCCGGGAGCGGCGGCUGCAGCGCGUCACGGCCACCGCGGGCGAAGACGUCCGCUUCCUCUGCCGCGCCGAGGGCGAGCCGGCGCCCACCGUGGCCUGGGUGACCCCCCAGCACCGGCCGGUGACGGCCACCAGCGCGGGCCGGGCGCGCGUGCUCCCCGGGGGGACGCUGGAGAUCCAGGACGCGCGGCCGCAGGACAGCGGCACCUACACGUGCGUGGCCAGCAACGCGGGCGGCAACGACACCUACUUCGCCACGCUGACCGUGCGCCCCGAGCCGGCCGCCAACCGGACCCCGGGCGAGGCCCACAACGAGACGCUGGCGGCCCUGCGCGCGCCGCUCGACCUCACCACCAUCCUGGUGUCCACCGCCAUGGGCUGCAUCACCUUCCUGGGCGUGGUCCUCUUCUGCUUCGUGCUGCUGUUCGUGUGGAGCCGCGGCCGCGGGCAGCACAAAAACAACUUCUCGGUGGAGUACUCCUUCCGCAAGGUGGAUGGGCCGGCCGCCGCGGCGGGCCAGGGAGGCGCGCGCAAGUUCAACAUGAAGAUGAUCUGAGGGGUCCCCAGGGCGGACCCUCCCCUCCCCUCCCCCGCGGGCCGGCCGCUCGCGUGUCCACCUAUGCAUUUCCCGGAGGGGAAGGGGACGGCUGCACGGCGCUCCCCAGGCAGAACUUCCCCUUUUUUUGUAGACGCCCAACCGCAGGACUGUUUUUCAUCAGCAUGCGUCUUUUUUGCAGUUUCUCAAGCGUUUUCUAAAGAUUUCAACCCGUCUUCCUGUCCCUGCUAUGGUGGCUGAGCUGGGGGGUGGGGGUGCGGGCUGCAAGGAUGGGGGGAUGGGCUCCCGUCUACCAACCCGGGGUGGCUGGGGGCGCUCAGAGACCCCAGGAUCCUCAGGGCCCGCAAUUCACACCCAGGAGGCACAAGACUGCUGCCCCCAAGCCCUGGGCUUCCGCUCCCCCAGCCCUUUGUACACAGAUCGCAUCGGGGAGACGGUGGACACCCGGGUCCCACAAAGGGCCCCACAGCCCCAAGGGGAGGGUGCGCAGAAAGUCUGCAUUGCUCACACCUGGCCGUCCUACACCUCACACCCAGAGACACACUCACACCUGGAACCCAAUCACACAGGUGCAACACACCUCACACCCAGCCGACACUAAAACCAGACCCGGGGCACCAGAGCUGACCGCAGGGGGCAGGCAGGGCUCUCGUGAGAGCAAAGCUCACACCCGGGACAGGCGCAACUCACACCCGGGACACACAGCUCACACCCAGGACACACACAGCUCACACCCAGAACACACAGCUCACACCCGGGACACACAGCUUACACCCGGGAAACACAGCUCACACCCGGGACACACAGCUCACACCCGGAACACAGAGCUCACACCCGGGACACACAGCUCAUACGCAGGACACACUCAGCUCACACCUGAUACAAGGACAGCUCACAGUGGAACACACAGCUCACACCCGGGAUACAGCUCACACCCAGGACACACUCAGCUCACACUGGAACACACAGCUCACACCCAGAACACAGAACUCACAUCUGGGACACACACAGCUCACACCCGAGACACACACCCUCACACCCAGCUGACACUAAAACCAAGCCCUGGGCACCAGAGCUGACCACAGAGGCAGGCAGGGCUCUCGUGAGAGCACAGCUCACACCAGGGACAUGCUCAGUUCACACCUGGGACAGGCACAACGCAUAACUGAGACACAGCUCACACCUGGGACACAGAGCCCACCCCAGCGCCUGCUCAGCUGAGCAUCUCCCAGCCGACCUCGGGGCCUGGGCUCAGGUCUUGCUGAGGACCCAGCACACACGGUGGUCACAGUCAGGGGUCCACACGCCCUGUCCUCCGUCCUCCCCACAGCCCAGCAGGGCUGUCCACAAGAAGGAGCCAUCACCCCAGCCCUCCGCCUCCCUCCGCUGCCACGUGCUUCCCAGAACAGCAGGCAAGAGAGGGCCACCCCACAAGGGAGAGGUGGCCACCCUGCCCCGGCCCAGAACCAUGGCUUCUGGGGUGCUGAGUGUCCUUCCAAAUGGGUCUACUGGAGGGACUUUUGCCCCUAGGUACACAUGACCUCUGAGCCGGCCUCAGACAAGCCCUGAGCGUGGCCCCAUCAUGGCCGGCCCUGCUGACCCGUGGCUCAGGUGGGGAACGAGACCAAAGAGCACAGGGGGUUCCCGGGGAUCCCGGCUACGUGCGGUGCAGUGUAGUGACAAGAACAAGGCCGGAACAAGGGCUUCACCCUGCAGGGAGGCCUGGACCCGGGUCCUCGGGAGAAGGUGAUGGAGGAAGCUGGGUCUCUGCACCUGCAGAGGUGGGGCAGAUCCAGGACCAAAGCUGGGGUCACAGGCCGACUGCAGCUCUGGUCAAGGAAGAGCUUCCCUGAGGUCACCGCCCGGUUGCUCUGCAGAUGGUGGGCAUCCUGUCACGGGGGGCAAACAAGCAGGAGCUGAGGUUUUGCAGAAGGAUUCAGGCACCAGACCGGGACCACAGGGACCAUCUGUGACCUGGCCUCCUCACAGCCAGUUCUUGCCCCUCCCCUCCACAUCCUCCAGAGGACAGUUAGGACAUUGCUGGGGGCAGGGACAGGAACCACUGUUGGGCCAAAACCUCAGCCAGAAAGGGGCUUGGCUGCCAACCAAGAGGUUAGGACAGACCCUCCAGGACUUUGCGGGAAGGGCUCAAAAGCAGCUCUGCUCCUGCCCGGCUAUGUGAUCUCAGCUGGUGACUGAAGACCACCUAGACCAUCAGUGUCCUCAUCUGUAAAAUGGGUCUGAGGGUCAAACCUAUUACCCUGUAUUCAGAGGCCAGGCCUGCAGAUGAGCUUGAUGGCUUGACUUGGAUCCUGGAUCCCUGAAGACUGCUCUGAGAUCGAUCAGCCAGAGAGAAACAGAGAGAAAGCUGGCUCAGCCCUGAAGGCUUUGAGCAAAAGUUUCAGAAGGAGCUGGAAGGAGACAACAGCCCGUUCUCCCUGAGCUGUGGCCGGGAGGGCCCAGGCCAGCACCACGAUGUACAGAUGGCCCAGGGGGCUCGACAUGAGUGAGGGCUGAAGUUCGUGCAACCCCAACCGCCACCCCUGAAUUGGGCAGAACCAAUUUUUUUCUUAGCACCUGUCUGACUCUGCUUACCAUGACAACCCCAAGGGCCCCCCAGAAUUGAUAUCCAAGUGCCUUUAGCCUAUCAAAGACAGGAGGGGGUGCAUUCUCGGCCAGGUUAGGGUUCACAGAGCAUCCGUAUAUUAGGAUUUCCCAGCCCCCUGAGCCCCCCACCCCAUCCCAACAUGAACUAAGACCCCUCAGCACCCCCACCCCUCAUCCUGCUGUAUUUGGUUCAAAUCCAAUAAAAAUGGAACCGAUUUAAUAACAAA